GAGUUCGCAGCUGCGCGCCGGGUCCUGGAGGCCGAGGCCGCUCCCGCCCGUUGUCCCCGCAGUCCCCGACGGGAGCGCCAUGGCCCAGCCGCCGCCCGACGUGGAGGGGGACGACUGUCUCCCCGCGUACCGCCACCUCUUCUGCCCGGACCUGCUGCGGGACAAAGUGGCCUUCAUCACAGGAGGCGGCUCUGGGAUUGGGUUCCGGAUUGCUGAGAUUUUCAUGCGGCACGGCUGCCAUACGGUGAUUGCCAGUAGGAGCCUGCCGCGAGUGCUGACGGCCGCCAGGAAGCUGGCUGGGGCCACCGGCCGGCGCUGCCUCCCUCUCUCUAUGGACGUCCGAGCGCCCCCAGCUGUCAUGGCCGCCGUGGACCAGGCUCUGAAGGAGUUUGGCAGAAUCGACAUUCUCAUUAACUGUGCGGCCGGGAACUUCCUGUGCCCCGCUGGCGCCUUGUCCUUCAACGCCUUCAAGACCGUGAUGGACAUCGAUACCAGCGGCACCUUCAAUGUGUCUCGUGUGCUCUAUGAGAAGUUCUUCCGGGACCACGGAGGGGUGAUCGUGAACAUCACUGCCACCCUGGGGAACCGGGGGCAGGCGCUCCAGGUGCAUGCAGGCUCCGCCAAGGCCGCUGUGGACGCGAUGACGCGGCACUUGGCUGUGGAGUGGGGUCCCCAAAACAUCCGCGUCAACAGCCUCGCCCCUGGCCCCAUCAGUGGCACAGAGGGGCUCCGGCGACUGGGUGGCCCUCAGGCCAGCCUGAGCACCAAGGUCACUGCCAGCCCGCUGCAGAGGCUGGGGAACAAGACCGAGAUCGCCCACAGCGUGCUCUACCUGGCCAGCCCUCUGGCUUCCUACGUGACGGGGGCCGUGCUGGUGGCCGAUGGCGGGGCAUGGUUGACGUUCCCAAACGGUGUCAAAGGGCUGCCGGAUUUCGCAUCCUUCUCUGCUAAGCUCUAGGAAUCUUCCGGCCGCUGCUUCCUGCCGCCUCACUCAGCCAGGUGGAGAGCACCAAUCUGAACCAGCAAUGCCUGCAGCCCAGCCCCUCCUCUGAACACUCAGCUAUUACUGCGCUUUCCCUCCCCACGGCCCCAACUCCAGGGCAGGAGCAACUGGACAGUGGGCCUGGCCCGUGGAGCUGCCACGCAGGUGCCUGAGGGCCAGGUGCCACGCAGGUGUCUGAGGACCAGGUGCCACGCAGGUGGUGGGGGUACAGACAAGAUGCUGGGAUGUCCCCUGCCCCAUGGUCAAGGGUGUCCUGCCUGCCUGGGUCCAGGGCCUGAGGGAGCCACAUGGAUCCCGAGACUUGUGUUCUCUUGGCUGAAAACACUGAGGUGCUCCCAUCUGUGCGUGGCCCAUGAGCUGGGAUGGUCCUCCAGCUGCCCACAAGGUCCGCCCCUCUGUCUCUGCACCACCUGUUUGCAUAAACACACUUUGCUACAAUCUUGCUAGUGCGUUUUCUUAAAAGAUAAUCUAUUUACUGUAAAAAUAAAUUGGACUUUGCAAAAGCUUUUAGAAGGAAAAGAAAGAGGAUUAAAGAGAAUUGCUGGUGA